AGGCCCAGGUCCCCAUCCAGGCCAACUUUGAUGCCAGCCAGGUGUGCCCAGCCCUGUUUCCUCCUCAUCUCCAAUGAGUCCUCCCGGCUUUGGUGCUGCACCCCGGGUCCCUGUCCACACCCUCUUUGAUCCAGGCUCAGCAGGGCUAGGGGCAGGGGAAACCCCCACCUCACCCGCUCCGUCUGACUGGAGUAGGGGUUGGCUGGGGAAGACUGCAGCCUCCAUCCUACCUUUUCAGUUGCAUCCCCCAACAAUCCCCAGGGCCCAAAAUAGGGACAAGUUGGUUGCCUGUGCCUCACUGUCCCCCACCCACCCCACAAAGACCUGUGACCUUGCCACAGCCCCACCCAUCCAGCCGUACCCCCUGGGUGCCAGCUGCAGACAGGCCGGUGCUGGGCUGGUGGGGGCCAGUUGCUCAUGUACUGAGGCCCCCCUCCCUCAGUUCUGCAUCGGGGUCGAGAUGUGUACAGCAGCCCCUGCCGUGGCCAGGAAGCAGCUGUGUCGGGGCAGAAUGUGGUGGGCUCAGGCCCAGGGCACAGGGGCGGCCUCCCAGCCUUCCCUGCACUUGCCCUGCAGUUCCAGGGCACCUGGUACAUGGUCGGGGUGGUGUCAGAUGACCAGGACUUCCUGGACUCCAAGGACACCAUGAAGAUGGCUGUGGUCUUAGUGACCCCCUUGGGGAAUGGUGACCUGGCCCUCAAGUUUGGAUACCCCACGCCCCAUGGCGGGUGCCAGAAAAUGGACACGACCUUCACCGAGGGUGCUGUACCGGGGCAGUUCAGCAACCCAGCCAUGGCCCUGAGUGACAUCCGAGUGGCCUUCUCCGACUACCAGCACUUUGCCUUGCUGUACUUGGAGAUGCGGAAAGGGGGCCUGCGGAACCAGUGGCUGCAGCUCUACGGUGGGCGGGCUGCGGGGCGGAGACCCAGACACCCCCGCUUCGGGUCUGGGAUGUCACCCCUGUGCCUGCACCAGCCCUUUCUGCACGCGGAAGGUGGAACCGCUGGCUCCUGGUGUCUGUGGCCGCGGGUCCCGGCCCCUCCCUGCCCCUCUCUCCCUCUCUUCGCCCCUCCAGCCCCUUCCCUUUAGCUUACCCGCCCUCCCCACCUUCAGCUCGAGCGCCCGAGCUGUUUCCCGAAGGCGCCCAGAAGAUGCAGCUACUGGCGCCCCAAGUGGGCCUGAGCCCCAGCCAGGGCGUCCUGCUGCCGAAGUCGGGUGAGCGGUGCCGGCAGCCCUGCUGGGAGGGCCAGGCCCCGGGUCACACCCCUGCUGGAAGGGCCAGGCCCUGGUCACUCCACUGAUCUCAGAUUCGGGACAGAAGUGCCCGGGGCAGACCCAGCCUGUCUGGGUCGGGGGAGGGCGAGACGUUGCCCAGGCCGGUGUUCCCAGGAGGAGAUCGCCUUGGGGCAGGUCGGGGGCCUCCGUCCCAGGGAAGGGGGCGCGGGGUGGCGCCUCAGGCUCGAUCUCUCUGCAGACCAGUGUGCGGGCGCGCUCUCCCGGGUGAGUAGACCAUGGCCAUGCGGAGCCGCGGACCAUGGGCCCUCCCAGCUCGGUGGGCUGCACCGCGGGGCCCUCUACCUUCGGGGCAGCUAGGGACGACAGCGGGGGUGAUGGGGCACCCGGGCGGAUCCGAGCCGCAGCAGCCUGGGGAACCGCGGGGCUGCGCGUCGGGAGGGGGCGGAGGCAGGGGACGCCGCCCACCUGCUCCUUGUUUUGCAGUGAGGGGUCCAGCCCCUGAGUGCCCGCAGGGGUCAGCUGCUCCGUGCGCCCAGCCCUGCCCAAAGAGCCCCCUCCCUCCACACCCUGGCCCCAAGCGCAAUAAACACCCUGAAUGCC